GCCUAUAUUUCUUUGGUUUUCAAUUACGAGUGGCUCUUCUCAGCAAGUGUUCCAUGAUGGUUGAGCCCUUCUUGGGAACCUGGAAGCUGGUCUCCAGUGAAAACUUUGAGGAUUACAUGAAAGAACUGGGAGUGAAUUUCGCAGCCCGGAACAUGGCAGGGUUAGUGAAACCGACAGUAACUAUUAGUGUUGAUGGGAAAAUGAUGACCAUAAGAACAGAAAGUUCUUUCCAGGACACUAAGAUCUCCUUCAAGCUGGGGGAAGAAUUUGAUGAAACUACAGCAGACAACCGGAAAGUAAAGAGCACCAUAACAUUAGAGAAUGGCUCAAUGAUUCACGUCCAAAAAUGGCUUGGCAAAGAGACAACAAUCAAAAGAAAAAUUGUGGAUGAAAAAAUGGUAGUGGAAUGUAAAAUGAAUAAUAUUGUCAGCACCAGAAUCUACGAAAAGGUGUGAAGAAAGGUCCACAGCAAUGAAAACUUGUUCACUGACAAGGAACUGGUACCUGAAGAAGAUAUGCCUCAGGGCUGGUGAUUUUUAAAAAAUGUCUCAAUAUAAAUUUGCUUAAUAAAAGCAUCAAAUUAAG